UCCAGACCCAAACAAUGUUCAUCUUACGUAUGUUGAGUGACGUCUCAAGUCUCCCCAAAAUGUAUAAAACUAAAUUGUGCUCUGACCACCUUGGGGACAUGUCAUUGGGAUCUCCUGAGGCUGUGUCACACCAUCAUCAUUGGCAAAAUAAACUUUCUAAAUUAACUGAGACCUUUCUCAGAUUUGGGGGGUUCAUAUUUUGGUAACCACAGAAGAAUUCUGACUGGAGGCGCCCCUGACCUUUGACAAAGCUAUCAGUGCUUGGUACCAGCUUGAGCUAUCUUUAUGGCUCAAACCAAUAGGACAAUUUGCUGAGGCCCGGAAGCACACCCUCCAGAGAAUACCUUAUCUUUCAAAAUCUGGUCAAGAUCUAAAGUUCAUUUUGUUGUACAACUCCUCUUUUUUUUUUGGAGUUUUACUUGCUUCUAACACAAGGAAGGCAAAUUUUUCCUGCUUCCAUGUUGAUGGAAGGCAGGUAACUCCUUUAUGGUGUUUGAGCUCGCAACCAACAGGGAAGAUGAGGGUUUUUCCCUGCUUCUAGGAUGGUAGAGAGCAGUCUUCAGCCUGAAACCCAUCCCUAGAGUCUUGCUGUGUCGCCAGGCUGGAGUGCAGUGGCACGAUCUCGGUUCACUGCAACCCCCGCCUCCCAGGUUCAAGCGAUUCUCCUGCCUCAGCCUCCCAAGUAGCUGGGACUACAGGCGUGCAUCACCAUGCCCAGAGUCAAGAAAACUUUUAAGCUAUUUACAACUUUUAACAAUUGAGUUAAGUAUACUCAAGAACAAAAUUCAGAGCAUAUUUGUUUCUCUCUACCUGAUUUCUACAGAUUUUGGAAACUAUUUGUGAGAUGCUGGCCAGUACAACUUUCUGCUCUGAUGGAACCAUGCUAGAUCUGCGCUUCCCACUUUGUAGCCAGUGGUCAUGCAUUGCUAUGGAGCAUUCAAAAUGUGGCUAAGUUCUGCCUUCAUAGUUCUCUGCCUUUGCCCAAAACUGCAGAAAAUGAACAAAUCCCAGGGAUCAGUUUCAUUCACGGAUGUGACUGUGGACUUUACCCAGGAGGAAUGGGAACAACUGGACCCCUCUCAGAGGAUCCUAUACAUGGAUGUGAUGCUGGAGAAUUAUAGCAACUUACUUUCAGUGGAAGUGUGGAAGGCUGAUGACCAGAUGGAGAGAGACCACAGAAACCCAGACGAGCAGGCGAGGCAAUUUUUAAUUCUUAAGAACCAAACCCCAAUUGAGGAAAGAGGCGAUCUCUUUGGAAAAGCACUUAAUCUGAACACAGACUUUGUUUCUUUAAGACAAGUACCUUAUAAAUAUGACUUAUAUGAAAAAACUUUGAAAUAUAAUUCAGACUUGCUUAAUAGUAAUAGAAGCUAUGCAGGAAAGCAGACUGAUGAGUGUAAUGAAUUUGGAAAAGCACUUCUCUACCUGAAGCAAGAGAAAACCCACAGUGGAGUAGAAUAUUCUGAAUACAAUAAAAGUGGAAAAGCCCUCAGCCAUAAAGCAGCCAUUUUUAAACAUCAGAAAAUAAAAAACUUGGUUCAACCUUUCAUUUGUACUUACUGUGACAAGGCUUUCUCCUUUAAGUCACUCCUCAUUAGUCAUAAGAGAAUACAUACUGGAGAAAAGCCAUAUGAAUGCAAUGUAUGUAAGAAAACCUUCUCCCAUAAGGCCAACCUCAUCAAACAUCAGAGAAUUCACACUGGGGAGAAACCUUUCGAGUGUCCGGAAUGUGGAAAAGCUUUCACCCACCAGUCAAACCUCAUUGUACACCAGAGAGCACAUAUGGAGAAGAAGCCCUAUGAGUGCAGUGAAUGUGGAAAGACAUUUGCCCAAAAGUUUGAACUCACCACACACCAGAGAAUUCAUACAGGAGAGCGACCCUAUGAGUGUAACGAAUGUGCAAAAACCUUCUUUAAGAAGUCAAACCUUAUCAUACAUCAGAAGAUUCACACGGGGGAGAAACGCUAUGAGUGCAGUGAAUGUGGAAAAUCCUUUAUCCAGAACUCACAGCUCAUCAUACACAUGAGAACUCAUACAGGAGAGAAACCCUAUGAAUGUACUGAGUGCGGCAAAACUUUCAGCCAGAGGUCAACUCUUAGAUUACACUUGCGAAUCCACACAGGAGAGAAACCAUAUGAGUGUUCCGAAUGUGGGAAGGCCUUUAGCAGGAAGUCCCGACUCAGUGUCCAUCAGAGAGUUCACAUCGGGGAGAAACCCUGAAACUCCAGCCAGGUCUUACUGUGGAAAACUCCUGCCAGAACUCUUCAAGCGGGUGAAAAACCUCAUGACAGUAUUGAGGGAACAUGGGAAUUCAUACUGAGAUGCAAUCUCUCAACUCAAAAAUGUAUUAAAAAUAGGAUCCCAUGAGAACAUUAUACUGGAAGUUACAUGUGAUACCCAGCUAAAGAAUACAUAUCAGAAUAUAUCCAGUUGUAAAUAGCCAUACCCAGUUGUACUACAAUGAGCUUUUUAAAAUCUUGAAUGAAUUGAGUAUUCUAGACAGCAGCAUAAGAAAUAUACAAACAGUAUCCUAUGAAUUUAGUGGUUUUAUGUGGAUAUGCCACAAAACACAAGUGGUAUGCUUUAGAUCUGCACAUGUGAAUUUAGCAUAAUCACUGGGAAUUUGAAAUUCUUGUCCUCUGUGAUAAUUAGGACAUAACAAGAUUUUCCAUACUAAACAUCACAUGUGUUUUUCAGUAUCUCUGCAAUCCAGUAUGCAUUCCAAAUGAAAUGUGUAACAUUUAAAGUAGCAUGGAACCUACGUCUUUCCCUACUGCUUGCUGGCAUAUAUCAGUUGGUAUGAACAUUGUUCUUGAGCUGCCUCUUAGGAAACAGAAGACAGUGUUGAAGUUUUCCCUGCUUCUGGUUUGCUGAAGAUUUUCUAGAAGCACUAUUUACACAAAUAUGCAAAUGUGAAAUAACCGAUCUAUAACGUGAAGGAGGCAGACAUGAGCUGUACUACUCAGUAUGCACCACAGAAUAAGAGUUUGCCGUGUAAAGACAAUAUCCCCAUUCGUCAUGCUCUUAUUUUCCCGUGGGAUAUUUGCAUACAAAUGCAUGUCUGUUACCAAAAUAUUGUGUAACACAGACAGAAACCACCUGUUUUUGUCUUUCCUUGUUUCCCUUAAUAUUUCAUGAAUUGUCUAGCAAAAAUGGUAGGAUGCUUCUGUAGUUCACAAAUGUUACAUUUCAGAGACUUUAGAGGAAAAAUUAUUUUAAAUAACUGUCAACUGUUUCAUUGCUUUUUAAAUUUUUCACGUGCAUAACCCCCUUUAGAAGUAAAUUUUUACACUAUUUUGUUGUUUAAAGGAGGCAUUUCUACUUCCUUGAGUUUUGCUGUUGCCAACCUAAAACAUUUCCCUUUGGAACAUGAGUUAUAAGUUAUUACUUUUCCUUUACAUGUUUACACUUUUAUAAAAAUCAGAUUUUUCAGUGGUCUCUCCAGAUAUUAACAAGAAUUGUUGUGUAACUCAAAGAUUUGCUUUUAUAGACUUGAUUUCAAAUUCUUAAGUUCAGCCUUUCCCUAUCAAUCACAAAUCAUGUAUUGGAAAUUAUAAAUGGCAACCAAAAACUGGCUUUUAAAAAAUAUUUUUGGAUAUCAUUGAUGUGCUGUCACACUAUAUAUUGAGUGACUUUCUGAACAAAUUUAUCCAGAACAUCCAUAGCCCAAUAAGCUUUUGUCUAAGUUGUCAUCUUACUUACUCACAAAGGAGGGGAAAACGUUAUUUUCAUAGCUGCUUUUAGAAAUGUAAAUUGUAACAGCCUCCUUGGACAACAUUGUGAGUCUGUUUUAACAUUAAUAUACUCUUACAACCUAGGAAUCUCCUGGGAAUCUAUCCCUAAGGAAUAAAAAGCGCCAGCACUUAAGAUUAUAUGUUUACUAAUGUAUAUUGUAUUUUUUGGUAAGGACCAAAAAAACAAACAAAAAAAAGACCAUCAGUAAGGGAAUGGAUGAAUAAAUUGUGGUAAAAACAUACCAUGGCUGAAUGGUAUUUCCUUGAAAAGAAUGUGUGGGAACAAACUCCAAACUUCUCUAGGUCAAAUGAGGAAAGCAAGAGGGGAGAGAGAGAGUGUAUGUGUGUGUGUAGCAGUUUUUAUAAAAUAAAGAUAAACCCUUAUA